AUGCAGAAUGGAUCUUCAGUCUUACUGGGCAUCAACUUUCCAUCCUCUGCACUAAAGAUGAUGGUCCCUGUCAGGGCUGAAGUUGAUCUAUCUGGGCCACGAGGCUGGGGAAGACCAGCAGGGGGUGGCCUGCGGGCAGGGGGCCCCCAUCUCCAACUGCGGGGGCAAGAGGCAUUUUCCAGCCGGCUCUGGACGAAGGGAGGGGAUAAGGAUGGGAAGGCAGCACCCCCCGGAGGCAGACGCCAAGAGCGGACGCGGCUGGCAGGCAGAGCCGACGGAUCCGCCGAGCUCAGGAAGUCCGGAGCCCGGGAGCAGCCCAACUCCGGCUCCGGGGCAGAGAGGGAGCCCGGGAGAAAGCAGCGGAGCCCACGCCCACGGGGCAGCCGAGUGAUUUACUUACAUGGCUGGCGGGCGGCGGCCACCUUCCCUCCCGCGUCCCGGGCGCACACACAACUUGCUGUCUUUCUCGGGCGGGAACAUCCACGGGAAACCGGACCGUCCUGCCCUUCUUUGCCUCUGUCCCUAACAGCCGCAGAACCCCGGGGCCCGACCUGGAAGAGCAGGGGUUGGCAGGAGGCGGAGGGUCUCCAGAAGCGGGCUGGCACCAGCGGAGACCCCCACUCCCGGCGAGUCCGCGGCGGCAGCUCUGGCGGAGCGCUGUGGGCGCGCGCGGGCGCCGGGGAUCGCACGCAGAGGAGCGGAUCUCCCUUUGGCAGGCGAGGCACGCACCGCCUCCUCCCCUCCGCUGCCCGGCCCUCCUCUUUCUCCAGUCCCCUCCCCUCGCGCCCCGGGGAACUCCGCGCAGACAGACCCAGGACGCACCGGGGACGUUCCUGGAGCGCCGGGAAGGGAGUGGGGGGGUGCCCCGCUGUCCGCGCGGGUCCAGGCCCACCCCCGGGGGCAGCUUUCGCGGCUCCUCCCCUAGCCCCGAGCCCCCUCGCGCCCCCUCUCCCUGCGUCUCAUUCAAAGCUGAGUGGGGAAGGCAGACAGACCGAGAAGUAUGGGAGAAAGUUGCUUGUCUUCCUGGGUGACCCCGAGGAGCCACGGAAGAUGACACACUUUGCCUGUUGGGGCUUUUCUGGGUUUACUGUUCGGGUUUAUGCUCCUGUUUUCCUGCCGCCGUUAAAAGAAGCCGUAGACGGGAAAGAGGGCCUUAAAGACCCAGAGAACAGUUGUGAUAGCACUUUGCAGCCCGGCAUUCAUUGUGCAGCCAUGAAGCAACAGGCAUGAGGAGGAAAGCCAGCACACGAACCAUGAUGGAGCAAAGUGGUGAAAAGAGUCCGCUUCUUCCCUAUCUGCACUAGGCUGUUGGACUUCUCUUGGGGUAAGAUCAAGAAUCCUCACCUGGUUAAGUCACUGUUAUUACCUGCUACACUAUUCAUACCAACUCUUCUGUUACACUCAAGAGGCCAGCACCACAACAAAGGCACAGAGUGUGGGGACAUGAAACAGAACCAGGAAAGAACAUAACAGUGUUGAGGGAGAAUUUCUCAAGCAAACAGUGGCUGGGGAGGCAUUCAUUGUCCACAGUGUGUAUUGCAGAAGAUGGACCCUCCUUAAAGUGUGGCAAUAGAAACAGGAACAGCUAUGAAAAUGGCUUAUAAAAUGUUUAUUCUUAAAGUCUCAACUUUGAGCAAUUCAGAGAGACAGAAAUUCUCAGCAUUAUAAAAUAGCCUGAUACGAAAAGGUUCCUCUUAAAUACAAACCAGCAAGAGAGAGAUGCAGACAGGUGGGAGGUCCAAAUGAGAACCAGUAGAUAACAAAAGAGAGGCUUUAAGUAGGGGCAGGGAGGAGAGAUUUUUUCCUUAACUUCUCCUGGAUGUGGAGCUCAUCAUUUCUUUGUCAAUAAAAAAAUACAUGAUUUGUUCCUCGACACAUGCUGCGAGAUAUCCCAAGAAAUGCUCCACCAGCUGAAAACCUACCAUCACAGUUUUCAGUACAGAUGCAGUGAACAAGGUUUAAAAAAACAUAGUUGGAGAUCAUAGUAAGUUCCUCCAUUCUGCCAUUUCCUUCCUCCCUUCAUUCCU